CUUGCCAUCAGAUUUAGGGUUCACUCCAGUCAUCCAGGAUGAUUUUAUCUUGAGAUUCUUAAUUAUGUCUCCAAAGACUCUUUUUUCAAAUAAAGUCACAUUCACAGGUUCUGUGGAUCAGGACAUGGACCUAUCUUUAUGGCAGCCACAAUUCCACCCCACUACACCCUCUGAGAACCCUGUCCCCCAGCUGAUCUGGCCUGGUCACGAUCUCUGGACCAUAGGGCACGCUUUUCACCAGGCUCUGUGGGUGUUGUUGUUGCUCCUCCGCUCCCCUGGAGGUCCUGCUUUUUUUCCUUGAACACUGCGAUCCCCUGCUCUCCCAUUCCCUCUCCAUGGGUCCUCUGACUGCUCCAGGGGAGAGGGACUCCCUUCCUCUUGGAAAGCUUCCUGCUGCUGCUCGGGUGCAGCUCGCUUGCCCCUUCCAGAGGCCCUGUGGGGUCUCUCGUCUGCACCUCCACACGGCCCUGGAAGCGGAGCCUGUGUUCCUGCUUCCCUGUGUUCCCUAUGGUGCCAGUGACAUGAGUAUAGAGACUCUGGGAAUACGUGUGGGGGAUAAUAGGGACCCGGAAAGUGGGCUCAGACACAUACUGAUAUUAUCAAAGUGAAGGCAAAUAGUAGACCUGCAGUCAUAGUCACCCUCAGUUGUAAGAAUACAUAUGUGUGGAUAUAGGCAGGGAAUUUAAAUUUGCUUUUUGUUUUUGGCAGGGAGCAGGUGUUAAAUCUAAUGAGCUUACAUACCAAGUGGGUUUAAAGAACAAUUGACAACCCCAGAGACAUGCAGGGCCUGGAAUCAAACAACAGGCUGGCUGCACUGCUCAGAAGGUCAGAGUCAAGGUCCUGGCUUUAUCCCGCUGAGGGCCACACCAUCUCUUAUGUGACCUCUGGAGUAAUAUAAGUGUCACAGGAAGGGCCUGAUCCCAGAAGGUUUGAGUUUCCGGUAAAAGCGUCAGGGCUGCCUCUGGUGGUGGAUCUCUCUGCGCGUCUUUUCCAGCCAGCAUCCCCCCGCACAUGGCUUCUGCUCCCCGGCAUCUCCAGCUUCCUCGCCAAUUCACUAAGGCUCCAGCCCCAGCCUGACUGGCUGGCCUUGCGGUUUGAAGAUUGAUCGUGUCCUGUGCUGAAGAUGUUUCCGGAACAACAGAAAGAGGAAUUUGUAAGUGUCUGGGUUCGAGAUCCUAGGAUUCAGAAGGAGGACUUCUGGCAUUCUUACAUUGACUAUGAGAUAUGUAUUCAUACUAAUAGCAUGUGUUUUACAAUGAAAACAUCCUGUGUACGAAGAAGAUAUAGAGAAUUCGUGUGGCUGAGGCAGAGACUCCAAAGUAAUGCGUUGCUGGUACAACUGCCAGAACUUCCAUCUAAAAACCUGUUUUUCAACAUGAACAAUCGCCAGCACGUGGAUCAGCGUCGCCAGGGUCUGGAAGAUUUCCUCAGAAAAGUCCUACAGAAUGCACUUUUGCUUUCAGAUAGCAGCCUUCACCUCUUCUUACAGAGCCAUCUGAAUUCAGAAGACAUUGAGGCGUGUGUUUCUGGGCAGACUAAGUACUCUGUGGAAGAAGCAAUUCACAAGUUUGCCUUAAUGAAUAGACGUUUCCCUGAAGAAGAUGAAGAAGGAAAAAAAGAAAAUGAUAUAGAUUAUGAUUCAGAAAGUUCAUCCUCUGGGCUUGGACACAGUAGUGAUGACAGCAGUUCACAUGGAUGUAAAGUAAAUACAGCUCCGCAGGAAUCCUGAAAAAUAAUUCUAAUGUUACUAUCUUAGGAAUAGCAAAUUAUGUCCAGUCAUAGAGAAGAAAGCUUCAUAAUAAUACAUUCUUACCUAAAGCUCACUGUCAUGAUGUUAGGUAUUUAAAUUCUUAAAGAUGUUGGGUUGUUUAUUAGUGGUAUUUUUAUGUUGUCUUAUUUUAGGUAAGCUUCUGUGUAAAGCUAAAAAUCCUGUGAAUACAAUACUAUCCUUUACAGGCAGACAUUAUUGGUAAACAAGAUCUUGCCCUCCAAUGAAAUGACUUACAUGUUUUAAAAAACCGAGUUGGUUUUAUUGAAUUUAAAAAGAUAGGUAACUAAGUAGCAUUUAAAAUCAAGAUAGAGCAUUCCUUCUUGUAUCAGUGGGGCAGUGUUACCAUAAACACGGUGUAUAUGUUGUUAAACCCUAUGAAGAGUAACAGUGUAGACCAGACUGCCUCUCUCAGAUAUGUGCCUGAUAUUUUGUGGAUACCUCCCCUGCACUGGCAAAACACUAUGCUUUUGGGUGUUAGACUGAAAUAUUUUAAGAGUAUUUAACCUUUCCAGUAUUCUGUUUCACGCUUAGAUGGAAAUGUAUCUUAUGAAUAGAGACAUAUUAAAAUAAUGUUUACAUCUUAGAAAAAACAUAGAUAGUGCUAGUAAUAUUACUUAUAACUGUAAUAUAUAGAUUCAGAAAUACAUUUUCAUUAUCCAAAAUCAGCUUCAACAAAUGGUUUCUGGAGACAAAUAAUUUGUUUUCAUUAUCAUUGUAUAAUCAGGUUAAUGAUUUAUUUUUUGACUAAAUGUGCAAUUUCUUAUCACUAGAUAACUUUCAGUAUCAGUGGUGGUUACUUAUUACUUAAAUCAGAGGAAGGAUUUUAUAAAGAUUAAUAAAUUUAAUUUUACCAAUAAAUAUUCCCAUAAUUUAGAAAAGGAUGUCGACUUGCUAAUUUCAGAAAUAAUUAUUCAUUUUUAAAAAGCCCCUUUUAAAGCAUCUACUUGAAGAUUGGUAUAAUUUUCAUAAAAUGUCUUUUUUUUUAGUGUCCCAAAGAUAUCUUAGAUAAACUAUUUUGAAGUUCAGAUUUCAGAUGAGGCAACAUUUUCUUGAGAUAAUUACCCAAGUUUCAUCCAUGUUGAAUGGUACAAAAUAUUUCUGUGAAACUAACAGGAAGAUAUUUUCAGAUAACUAGGAUAACUUGUUGCUUUGUUACCCAGCCUAAUUGAAGAGUGGCAGAGGCUACUACAAAAAGCAACCUUUUCAUUUUCACUAAGAGUUUAAAAGCUAUUGUAUUAUUAAAAAGUCUUUACAAUGCUUGUUUCAAAGAACCAACAGAAAAAAAAGCUAAGAAAACUGAGAACUAACAUUAAAAAAAUUAAAUUUAGAAUAAGAAUGAUUUCUUUAAUUUGUCCUUUUUUUCUUUGGUCUAAAACAUUAUUAAAUUUUUGUAAAUAUUUUGAUUUAAUGUGUCUUAGAUCCUCAUUAUUUUAAUACAGGAAAAGAAAAGAUUUAGUAAUUUCUUACCAUGCUAAUAUGUAAAGUUCAUGCCAUCCAGGCAUUUAAGAGCGAUCCUCAUCCCUUCAGCAAUAUGUAUUUGAGUUCACACUAUUUCUGUUUUACAGCAGUUUUGAAAAACACAUACUAUGCCACCAAUUGUCAUAUUAUUUUUAGAUGAUGUAACAUAGCCAUCAAAAUUAAUAUUAUGUAAUGCCUAAUACUUAGUAUGUAAAUGUCACGAGAUCAUUUUUACAUUAAACGUGAAAAAAAAUCAACUUUGCCGGAUCACUUAUUUUAUACAAGAGAAUAUAUUCUGCCUUAGACCCAAA